AGAGUCGCCGAGGUCGUCCCCGGCACCGGAAGUGACCCUGGCGGGUUUGUCUUCAAAUUCUCGGCGAGCAGGAGCCGCGCCGGCAGGUGGUGUUGACGAUUGAACUGGGCAGUACUGGGGCCGUGAGCGGAGAGCAAAGUGGGCUGGACUGGGUCAGGCCCUCCUUCCUCGCUGCCGGGAUCUCCACUCCGCCAAUCCCCUGUGCCUGGCGUUGGGCGGUUUCCCGAGGAGCUUGGGCCGCCGCAGAGAUGAACAUUCUGAAAAUUACUUACCAAUGUAUGGCCACUUUUGAAGUCAUAUACACUUGCUUUACUGAAAUGCCUUCAGGAAGAUGCAUGAUUGGGCUUCGUGAUCUUUUUGUUUUAGGAGCUUACAGUUGAACAUGAGUCUUCUUAUGAUUAGUGAGAAUGUAAAAUUGGCUCGUGAAUAUGCAUUGCUGGGAAACUAUGACUCUGCGAUGGUCUAUUAUCAGGGAGUUCUUGACCAAAUGAACAAGUAUCUGUACUCAGUCAAAGAUACAUACCUCCAGCAGAAAUGGCAACAGGUUUGGCAGGAAAUAAAUGUGGAAGCUAAACAUGUUAAAGAUAUCAUGAAAACACUAGAGAGCUUUAAACUGGACAGCACUCCCUUGAAAGCGGCACAGCAUGACCUUCCAGCUUCUGAGGGAGAAGUCUGGUCCAUGCCUGUACCUGUUGAACGAAGACCCUCACCAGGACCUAGAAAACGCCAAUCUUCUCAGUACAGUGACCCUAAAUCACAUGGUAAUCGUCCAAGUACAACUGUCAGAGUUCACCGUUCAUCUGCACAGAAUGUUCACAAUGACAGAGGGAAAGCUGUUCGUUGUCGUGAAAAGAAAGAACAGAAUAAAGGAAGAGAGGAAAAGAACAAAUCACCUGCUGCAGUAACAGAACCAGAGACAAAUAAAUUUGAUAGUACCGGAUAUGAUAAAGACUUAGUAGAAGCUUUGGAAAGAGAUAUAAUUUCCCAGAAUCCCAAUGUUCGAUGGGAUGAUAUCGCUGAUUUAGUAGAAGCUAAAAAGUUGCUUAAGGAAGCCGUAGUGUUACCAAUGUGGAUGCCCGAAUUCUUUAAGGGCAUUAGGAGACCAUGGAAAGGAGUACUGAUGGUCGGCCCACCUGGCACGGGGAAGACGCUCCUUGCUAAAGCAGUAGCUACAGAAUGCAAGACAACAUUCUUCAAUGUCUCUUCAUCAACUUUGACUUCCAAAUACAGAGGAGAAUCUGAGAAGCUUGUUCGUCUUCUGUUUGAAAUGGCUCGAUUUUAUUCUCCAGCCACCAUAUUUAUUGAUGAGAUAGACUCCAUCUGUAGUCGCCGAGGGACUUCUGAAGAACAUGAAGCAAGCAGAAGGGUGAAAGCGGAGCUGCUGGUUCAGAUGGAUGGUGUUGGAGGUACUUCUGAAAAUGAUGACCCUUCCAAAAUGGUUAUGGUUCUGGCAGCUACUAAUUUUCCCUGGGAUAUAGAUGAGGCUUUAAGACGACGCCUUGAGAAACGAAUCUAUAUUCCUUUGCCGUCAGCAAAAGGCAGGGAGGAGCUAUUACGAAUAAGUCUACGUGAGUUGGAAUUGGCUGAUGAUGUUGACCUUGCAAGUAUAGCAGAAAACAUGGAAGGUUAUUCAGGUGCGGACAUUACCAACGUGUGCAGGGAUGCGUCCUUGAUGGCAAUGAGAAGGCGCAUUGAAGGUUUGACUCCAGAGGAAAUCCGAAAUCUUUCCAAAGAAGAAAUGCACAUGCCUACAACUAUGGAGGAUUUCGAGAUGGCUUUAAAAAAGGUUUCUAAGUCAGUGUCUGCUGCAGACAUUGAAAGAUACGAGAAAUGGAUAUUUGAGUUUGGAUCAUGCUAAAUUCUCACAUGUAAACUGUGAGAAAUGUGCCUUAAGUGUUUGAAUAUUAAAUGCAGUAAUUCAUUGUACUGAGUGCUAUAUUUUUUUUAACUUUCAUAAUGGUAAGAUUUUUUUAAAAAAACCCUUAUGAUUCUGAAUAAAGGCAAUAUUUUUAAGCUGAAAA